AGGCAAACCCCAGCCUUGGACUGGCCCUCUCUGAUCUCUGAGGCCAGGCUCUAAUGUGAUUUGAAUCUACUUCUAACCCCUUCCAAGCACUGCCCUCCCGAAUUCUCUGCUCCUCUCCCCACCCCACUGUUGGUCUGUGAUUUCGAGGCAGGCGUGGCCCCCUGCAGCCUGGAAUGAAGUCACUGGGGCUGUUUGGAGACCGGGGCUGUUUGGAGGACAAGGGCACACAACUGGUUCCGUUAAGCCCCUCUCUUGCUCAGACGCCAUGGAGCUGGAUCUGUCUCCACCUCAUCUUAGCAGCUCUCCGGAAGACCUUUGCCCAGCCCCUGGGACCCCUCCUGGGACUCCCCGGCCCCCUGAUACCCCUCUGCCUGAGGAGGUAAAGAGGUCCCAGCCUCUCCUCAUCCCAACCACCGGCAGGAAACUUCGAGAGGAGGAGAGGCGUGCCACCUCCCUCCCCUCUAUCCCCAACCCCUUCCCUGAGCUCUGCAGUCCUCCCUCACAGAGCCCAAUUCUCGGGGGCCCCUCCAGUGCAAGGGGGCUGCUCCCCCGCGAUGCCAGCCGCCCCCAUGUAGUAAAGGUGUACAGUGAGGAUGGGGCCUGCAGGUCUGUGGAGGUGGCAGCAGGUGCCACAGCUCGCCACGUGUGUGAAAUGCUGGUGCAGCGAGCUCACGCCUUGAGCGACGAGACCUGGGGGCUGGUGGAGUGCCACCCCCACCUAGCACUGGAGCGGGGUUUGGAGGACCACGAGUCCGUGGUGGAAGUGCAGGCUGCCUGGCCCGUGGGCGGAGAUAGCCGCUUCGUCUUCCGGAAAAACUUCGCCAAGUACGAACUGUUCAAGAGCUCCCCACACUCCCUGUUCCCAGAAAAAAUGGUCUCCAGCUGUCUCGAUGCACACACUGGUAUAUCCCAUGAAGACCUCAUCCAGAACUUCCUGAAUGCUGGCAGCUUUCCUGAGAUCCAGGGCUUUCUGCAGCUGCGGGGUUCAGGACGGAAGCUUUGGAAACGCUUUUUCUGCUUCUUGCGCCGAUCUGGCCUCUAUUACUCCACCAAGGGCACCUCUAAGGAUCCGAGGCACCUGCAGUACGUGGCAGAUGUGAACGAGUCCAACGUGUACGUGGUGACGCAGGGCCGCAAGCUCUACGGGAUGCCCACUGACUUCGGUUUCUGUGUCAAGCCCAACAAGCUUCGAAAUGGCCACAAGGGGCUUCGGAUCUUCUGCAGUGAAGAUGAGCAGAGCCGCACCUGCUGGCUGGCUGCCUUCCGCCUCUUCAAGUACGGGGUGCAGCUGUACAAGAAUUACCAGCAGGCACAGUCUCGCCAUCUGCAUCCAUCUUGUUUGGGCUCCCCACCCUUGAGAAGUGCCUCAGAUAAUACCCUGGUGGCCAUGGACUUCUCUGGCCAUGCUGGGCGUGUCAUUGAGAACCCCCGGGAGGCUCUGAGUGUGGCCCUGGAGGAGGCCCAGGCCUGGAGGAAGAAGACAAACCACCGCCUCAGCCUGCCCAUGCCAGCCUCCGGCACGAGCCUCAGUGCAGCCAUCCACCGCACCCAACUCUGGUUCCACGGGCGCAUUUCCCGUGAGGAGAGCCAGCGGCUUAUUGGACAGCAGGGCUUGGUAGACGGCCUGUUCCUGGUCCGGGAGAGUCAGCGGAACCCCCAGGGCUUUGUCCUCUCUUUGUGCCACCUGCAGAAAGUGAAGCAUUAUCUCAUCCUGCCGAGCGAGGAGGAGGGCCGCCUGUACUUCAGCAUGGAUGAUGGCCAGACCCGCUUCACUGACCUGCUGCAGCUCGUGGAGUUCCACCAGCUGAACCGCGGCAUCCUGCCGUGCUUGCUGCGCCAUUGCUGCACGCGGGUGGCCCUCUGACCAGGCCGUGGACUGGCUCAUGCCUCAGCCCGCCUUCAGGCUGCCCGCCGCCCCUCCACCCAUCCAGUGGACUCUGGGGCGCGGCCACAGGGGACGGGAUGAGGAGCGGGAGGGUUCCGCCACUCCAGUUUUCUCCUCUGCUUCUUUGCCUCCCUCAGAUAGAAAACAGCCCCCACUCCAGUCCACUCCUGACCCCUCUCCUCAAGGGAAGGCCUUGGGUGGCCCCCUCUCCUUCUCCUAGCUCUGGAGGUGCUGCUCUAGGGCAGGGAAUUAUGGGAGAAGUGGGGGCAGCCCAGGCGGUUUCACGCCCCACACUUUGUACAGACCGAGAGGCCAGUUGAUCUGCUCUGUUUUAUACUAGUGACAAUAAAGAUUAUUUUUUGAUACA